GUUGCUGGGUGUCCCAGGGCCUGAGGCAGGACGGUACUCCGCUGACACCUUCCCUUUCGGCCUUGAGGUUCCCAGCCUGGUGGCCCCAGGACGUUCCGGUCGCAUGGCAGAGUGCUACGGACGACGCCUAUGAAGCCCUUAGUCCUUCUAGUUGCGCUUUUGCUAUGGCCUUCGUCUGUGCCGGCUUAUCCGAGCAUAACUGUGACACCUGAUGAAGAGCAAAACUUGAAUCAUUAUAUACAAGUUUUAGAGAACCUAGUACGAAGUGUUCCCUCUGGGGAGCCAGGUCGUGAGAAAAAAUCUAACUCUCCAAAACAUGUUUAUUCUAUAGCAUCAAAGGGAUCAAAAUUUAAGGAGCUAGUUACACAUGGAGACGCUUCAACUGAGAAUGAUGUUUUAACCAAUCCUAUCAGUGAAGAAACUACAACUUUCCCUACAGGAGGCUUCACACCGGAAAUAGGAAAGAAAAAACACACGGAAAGUACCCCAUUCUGGUCGAUCAAACCAAACAAUGUUUCCAUUGUUUUGCAUGCAGAGGAACCUUAUAUUGAAAAUGAAGAGCCAGAGCCAGAGCCGGAGCCAGCUGCAAAACAAACUGAGGCACCAAGAAUGUUGCCAGUUGUUACUGAAUCAUCUACAAGUCCAUAUGUUACCUCAUACAAGUCACCUGUCACCACUUUAGAUAAGAGCACUGGCAUUGGGAUCUCUACAGAAUCAGAAGAUGUUCCUCAGCUCUCAGGUGAAACUGCGAUAGAAAAACCCGAAGAGUUUGGAAAGCACCCAGAGAGUUGGAAUAAUGAUGACAUUUUGAAAAAAAUUUUAGAUAUUAAUUCACAAGUGCAACAGGCACUUCUUAGUGACACCAGCAACCCAGCAUAUAGAGAAGAUAUUGAAGCCUCUAAAGAUCACCUAAAACGAAGCCUUGCUCUAGCAGCAGCAGCAGAACAUAAAUUAAAAACAAUGUAUAAGUCCCAGUUAUUGCCAGUAGGACGAACAAGUAAUAAAAUUGAUGACAUCGAAACUGUUAUUAACAUGCUGUGUAAUUCUAGAUCUAAACUCUAUGAAUAUUUAGAUAUUAAAUGUGUUCCACCAGAGAUGAGAGAAAAAGCUGCUACAGUAUUCAAUACAUUAAAAAAUAUGUGUAGAUCAAGGAGAGUCACAGCCUUAUUAAAAGUUUAUUAAACAAUAAUAUAAAAAUUUUAAACCUACUUGAUAUUCCAUAACAAAGCUGAUUUAAGCAAACUGCAUUUUUUCACAGGAGAAAUAAUCAUAUUCGUAAUUUCAAAAGUUGUAUAAAAAUAUUUUCUAUUGUAGUUCAAAUGUGCCAACAUCUUUAUGUGUCAUGUGUUAUGAACAAUUUUCAUAUGCACUAAAAACCUAAUUUAAAAUAAAAUUUUGGUUCAGGA